UUCGGGCAGUGGAGAUCGCCCUAAGAACCUGUGAGCUUAGAAACAGCUUUCAGAGACCAGAAGGAGGCCUGGGGCCCGUCGGGAAGUUUGCUGAAGGAACUAAGAGUGGAAACAAUCUCUGACUGCACACAAGUGCAUUUGUGAUCCACCACAGGCACGUUUUUGUCAAUUGGCUGGGGAAGCCCAACCCAUCUAACCUCCUGGACUCUGGAAAGGCAUUCUCCGGGUCUGGUUUCUCACACAUUACACAGCAGAGGUUUGGAGUUAGUUCACAGAAAAGUUAACAUCCCGGAACAGUGCAGAAGGCUUGGGUUUCAGUUUGCUAGGGCCCCCAUAACAAAAUGCCACAGAACCAGGUGGUUUAAACAACAGAGAUUUAUUUUCUCACAUUUGGAGGCUAGAAGUUCAAGAUCAAGGUGUCAGCAGGCCUGGUUUUUCCUAGAGGCCUCUUUUGUUGGCUUGCAGACAGCUGUCUUCUCACUGUGUCCUUGUGCGGUCUUCCCUCCAUGCACACACAUCUCUAAGUUUCAUUAUGUGCCCAACGUUCCUCUUCUAAGAACACCAGUUGGACUGGAUUUUAACUUUAACCAGCCUCAUUUAAGUUAAUCACCUCUUUAAAUGCUCAAUCUCCAAGUACAGUCUCAUUCUGAGGUUCCAGGGGUUUCUCAACGUAAGAAUUUAGGGGGACAGAAUUCAGCCCGUAGCAGCUGGGCAGCAGGACUCAUGGGUCCCAGUUCUCAGGCCCCAAGGACUCAGAGCAGCAAAGGAUACGUGACACAAGCAGGGCUGAACUGGACACCAGACUUUCUUUGGGGUUGUAAAAGGAGAAGUGUGACUCCACUGCCAAGGGUAAGCACUCUUGUCUUAUGCUACCCUUUAUUCUUGAACCUUGGGGCAGCCUGUGUCUCCCUUCCCUAAACGUCAUCUGUUCCGUUUUUCCAGUCUUCCAGACCUGGUCCUUGGACUGGAGACCUUCACCCUUCCUAUUUUGUGGCUUUCUCUUCAAAUCCACCUCGUCCUUCCUCCAUGACUUAUAAGUCAUCAUCUCUGCUGGUUUCUGAAAUGAGAUAUGCUUCUUGGGGUCUUCAGUGAAGAGGAAUAGCAAGUGAAAGGAGGAUGGUGGCAGGGUACAUGAACCCCUACCAGGCUUCUAGGCUUCCCCUGCAUGGCAGCCAGCCUCUAAGUUGGCCCCCAACCAUCCCUGCCUUCUUCUAUUCACACCCUUGUGUGGUUCCUUCCCACAUUGAAUAGGCCUGACUUGUGUAACCACUACACUAUUGAAGAAAUGAGAGUUUGACUUCUGAGGGUAAGUCAUAAAAUACAUCGUGGCUUCUGUCUUGUUUUCUUUGAUCGCUUACUUUGGGGGAAGCCAGCUUCCAGGUCAUGAAAAUACUCAAGCAGCCUUAUGGAGUGCUCCACAUGACAAGGGAUCGAGGCCUCCCACCAAUAGCCAUGGGAGUGUGCAAUCUUGAAAGCUGGUCCUUCAAUUCCAGCCAAGCAUUCACAUGACCGCAAUCCUAGCUGAUCUCGCUUGUGACCUCUAUGGGAGACCCUAAGCCAGAACCACUCAGAGAAGCUGCUCCGGAACGUCAGACACACAUGAACUGUGAGAUAGUAAACGUUUAUUGUUUAAAGCUACUUGGUUUGGGGAUAAUUUGCGUUUCAGCAGUAGACAAUAUAUUUAUUUUGUCCAGGGGAGUGGAAAGGCGAUUACAGAGUUUGUUGAGCCCCAUAGAGUCCUAGUCUUUGCUUAAAGAAAUAUACCAGUUCUUUCUAAUACAGAAUCCAUUAAGUUCGUUGGUUGCAAACAAUAGAAACCAACUCUGCCUCACUUAUGUUUAUUGGAGGCCAUAAGAGAGCCACAGCAUCUACCAAAAAGCCAAAAAAAAAACAGGUUUUGGAAAAGACAGGAACUAGCUACAGGAGCUAAUGGCCAAUCUUGUCUGAGUUCUUUGAUGGCGACACAUGAACUACAGCCGUUUUGUUGUUGUUAAUUUCUCCGUGUUUUCCCCUCAGUUUUGGAUGACUCUGCUCAAGGUUCAGAUUCUGAGGAGCAAGUAUCUGUUGGGCUAUCUGAGGUCCUGCUACCAUUCCUUGGCCAGUAAUAGGUAGUUUCACAGGGAUUAUAUGCAAUGGAGGAAAAGUUGUUCUCAAGGAAAACUAGGGAGCUUUCUCCAGAAGAUGAUGUAAUGGCAGAAACAACAGGUGGUUGACCACAGAAGGGGACAAUAAUAAUACUUGUAAUUUAUUGUGCGCUUAUAUGAGCCUCACCCUCUCCCAGGUGUCAGAUAAUGCUCGUAAAUGCCUUAGUCCAUCAUCUCAGUAAAUUUUUUUUAUAACACUAUGAGAGAAGCAGUAUUUUUUUUUUCUGUUACAGAUAUGGAAACCGAGGUUCUGAAAAGUUAACUAAAACUUCCGAGGUUAUAGUACGAGGCAAAACCAAGAUUUAAACUCAGAUCUGUGCCGAUCCAGAGUCCAAGCUUAACUCUGAUCUACUGAGUGUUGUCAGAGCAUCUGUUUCUAAGACAUUAAGAAUGGUUAAAAGGAGCUUCUUGGCUCAUGGUCAAGCUGCCUUUCUCUUUAUCUCUGCAGUUGGCCAACAGCUGCCCUAGCCCUGAAGACAAAGCCACAGACCCAAGCAUGUCGGAACAGGAUUGGUCAGCUAUCCAGAAUUUCUGUGAGCAGGUGAACACUGACCCCAAUGGCCCCACACAUGCGCCCUGGCUACUGGCCCACAAGAUCCAGUCUCCGCAAGAGAAGGAAGCUCUUUAUGCCUUAACGGUGCUGGAGAUGUGCAUGAACCACUGUGGGGAGAAGUUCCACAGCGAGGUGGCCAAAUUUCGUUUCCUGAACGAACUGAUCAAAGUGUUGUCCCCAAAGUACCUGGGGUCCUGGGCCACAGGAAAAGUUAAAGGAAGAGUCAUUGAAAUACUCUUCAGUUGGACAGUCUGGUUUCCGGAAGACAUCAAGAUUCGAGACGCUUAUCAGAUGCUGAAGAAACAAGGAAUUAUAAAACAAGACCCUAAACUACCAGUGGAUAAAAUCUUACCCCCACCAUCUCCCUGGCCCAAGAGCUCCAUCUUUGAUGCUGAUGAAGAAAAGUCCAAGCUUCUGACAAGGCUUCUAAAGAGCAACCACCCCGAGGACCUUCAGGCUGCAAACCGGUUAAUCAAGAAUUUGGUCAAGGAGGAACAAGAAAAAUCGGAGAAGGUGUCCAAGAGGGUCAGUGCGGUGGAGGAAGUGCGAAGCCAUGUGAAGGUGCUGCAGGAGAUGCUGAGCAUGUACCGCAGGCCAGGGCAGGCCCCGCCCGACCAGGAGGCCCUGCAGGUCGUGUAUGAGAGGUGUGAAAAGCUGCGGCCCACGCUGUUCCGGUUGGCGAGUGACACCACUGAUGACGAUGAUGCACUCGCGGAAAUUCUCCAGGCAAAUGACCUCCUCACCCAAGGAGUUCUGCUGUACAAACAGGUGAUGGAGGGCCGGGUCACCUUUGGAAACAGAGUGACCAGCUCAUUGGGAGACAUCCCUGUCUCCAGAGUCUUUCAGAAUCCAGCAGGCUGCAUGAAGACCUGCCCCCUGAUUGACUUGGAGGUGGACAAUGGACCUGCGCAGAUGGGGACUGUGGUGCCAUCUUUGCUUCAUCAGGACCUGGCAGCCUUGGGAAUCAGUGAUGCUCCUGUUACAGGCAUGGUUUCUGGUCAGAAUUGCUGUGAGGAAAAGAGGAAUCCCUCCUCCAGCACGCUGCCAGGCGGUGGUGUUCAGAACCCUUCUGCAGACAGGAAUUUGCUGGACCUCCUCUCAGCACAGCCAGCUCCGUGCCCUCUGAAUUAUGUUUCGCAGAAAAGUGUCCCCAAGGAAGUGCCACCAGGUACUAAGUCCUCUCCAGGUUGGUCCUGGGAGGCUGGCCCGUUGGCUCCUUCCCCAUCUUCACAGAAUACACCUCUGGCUCAAGUGUUUGUCCCUUUGGAGUCUGUUAAGCCCAGCAGCCUGCCGCCUCUCAUUGUGUAUGACCGGAAUGGAUUCAGAAUUCUGCUCCACUUCUCCCAGACGGGAGCCCCUGGGCACCCAGAGGUACAGGUGCUGCUCUUGACCAUGAUGAGCACGGCUCCCCAGCCUGUCUGGGAUAUCAUGUUUCAAGUGGCUGUGCCAAAGUCAAUGAGAGUGAAGCUGCAGCCGGCAUCCAGCUCCAAGCUUCCUGCAUUCAGUCCUUUGAUGCCUCCAGCUGUGAUAUCUCAGAUGCUGCUGCUUGACAAUCCACACAAAGAACCUAUCCGCUUACGGUACAAGCUGACAUUCAACCAAGGUGGACAGCCUUUCAGCGAAGUAGGAGAAGUGAAAGACUUCCCAGACCUGGCUGUCUUGGGCGCAGCCUAACUUUUCACAAGAUGGACCCUUCAUUUCAAGCUUAGGCUGGCGUUACUUUUGCUGUCUAGUCAGGACUAAUCACGGUGUUUCAGUGCGGAGUGCCAAGAGUCCUAUCCUGACGUCAGGCUCUGGGUGUCAACCUCUGACUUAUUCUGCAGAUGCUCUGUGUGUGUGUGUGUGUGUGUGUGUGUGUGUGUGUGUGUGUGUGUGUUCGGGGAGAGGGUGGUAGCACAGGGCUUGGGAUAUCGGCAGUGUGGGAAAUGCGAAGCAUUUCUCAUCAUCAUCAUCUCUGCUACAGUCAUGUUUCUGCAUGUCAGCGAGCGACACUGUCCCUGCCUCAGGUUGGAGGUUUUAUCAGCCAAAGUGUUUUUUUCAUGUAUCGUUCGUUCCAUUCAUCCACUCUGUGCCUUGUCAGCCUUUGAAAGGCUUGGUUGCUCCCAGGCUGCUGUUCUCAGGGACCUUAAAAGGGACCUGGUUAGUCUUGGGGCAGAGAGUAUCUACUUGGGCACUCUCUUCCAAGAAAGACCUUGUCUCCAUUUUCAUUAGACAAUGCUUCUUGUGUGUGUUCUGGAAGAUCUUCUAAAUGGAAUGCUUGUUGCACUGUUCCCAGGCGAGUGGCUGCCAUGAGACCUGAGGACCACACUUGGGGGACCAAUCAUGUCCUUCACCACUGUGCCUUAGAAUCGCCCCUGGACAGAGUUCCUGGGCAGAGGGGAAAGCAGCUCCCAGGCCUUACUCAGGCCUCAGGUCCAUGGGUUGGGCAGCCAGUCUGGGCCCUUCUCAGGAUCCUCAUCUCCAUCCUCAUCCUCUUCCUUCACAGCAUUUACUUGGAGCUCUUUGUGACACACCAUGUCAGUCAUGAUGAAUCGGCCAACAGCCAGCCCUUGCCAGCUGACGUCACAGUCUAAGAUGGGAAACUGUGGUACAGAUAGACAUGAAGAGAGCUUAGCAGUGAUUGAGGUGGUGACUAAAUAUACAGUCAUUGAAUAAAUACCAUGUAGCAAGUGUACUUUGUGGAGUGUUGAGUAAGUGGAAAAUGGAAAGCCAGUUGCAUUUAGAGAUGAUAGGCCUAAAGGGAACUGUCUUCUGUCGAGAAGUAAAGGAAACUUCAUGAAGGAUGUAGAAGCUUAGCUGCCUCAGAGAAGAGAGAACCUGAAGAUCUGAGGCAAGCUGGACAGGAGAGGUGGAUAUUUGUUGAUGGAAGAAUUCAAGUUUAUAAUCAAUUCCCACUUAGCACCUACUGUGUGCUAGGAACUUGAAUGUGUAUGUUUGACAAGUCCUGCUUGGCCUGAUGGGUGGGAGAAGGAACCUGAGCCUGGCUGAGAUGGCUAGGCGGAGGGCUUUGAAGUCCAAGCAGCUGAACUGGCUGGGUGGGUUUCUACCUUUGAAACUGCAAGACUUGUUUGGAGCUCUUAAUUACAAUAUCUGAUAUUUUUACAGUCUGAUCUUUUGACUUCUACAUAUAGUGGAAAUCUGCCAAUACUAAUUGGUGGAGAUGGGAACUGUAAAAGAUCAAGUAUGCUAAUUUUAAGCAAAUGUAAAAACUCAUAAAACAGGUAAACAGUGGGGUGAUUUCAUUUGCCAUAAUUCACAUAAGACGAAUUUUAAUCUAAAAGUACUUUCUUGCUUGUAUUCUGUGUGGCUUUUUUUUGUUUUUUGAGGCCAUAUCUCACUCUGUCACUCAGGCUGGAGUGCGGUGGUAUAAUCUCAGCUCACUGCAAUCUCUGCCUACCAGGUUCAAGCGAUUCUCGUGCCUCAGCCUCUCGAGUAGCUGGGACUACAGGCGUGAGCCAGCACGCCCAGCUAAUUUUUGUAUUUUUAGUAGAGACAGGAUUUCACCAUGUUGGCCAGGCUGGUCUCGAACUCCUGACCUCAGGUGAUCCGCCUGCCUUGGCCUCCCAGAGUGCUGGGAUUACAGGCGUGAGCCACCGCACCCGGCCUCUGUGUAGCUUUUAUAGGCUCUGUUACUGUUGCGUAGUCUUGAAGAGGUACCCAUCAUAAUGACAGCAUCUCCCUCUGAAGGGUUUUGGUCAAAAUGGGUGAAUGAGACUUAUACAUAAAGACAGGCUUUCUCCCCUAUAGUUAGGAGGUGAACUCACACAUGUGUACCUGAACAUUCUUGCUUUUGAGGAGACAGACUCCCAGUGGUACUACUAUGCUUAGGUGUUGGACAGGAUAGGGGUAGGAGGAGAGGAGGCAGGCUGCUGUCCUGAAAGUGGCUGUGGUUUAUGGCAUCACUCCCUUCUAAUCAGCAAGUCCAGUGGCCACUUAGAGCCCAGCUCCUACCUCUUCAUUCACUUAACAAGUAGUUAUUGGCUGUGCACAGUGGCUCACGCCUAUAAUCCCAGCAUUUUGGGAGGCUGAGUGGGAUGACCGCUUGAGCCCAGGAUUUCAAGUCCAGCCUGGGCUACAUAGUGAGACCGUGUCUCUGUUUUUUUAAAAGCUAGUUGUUGACCAGCUACCCUGAGCCAGGCACCACCCUGAAGGAGCUUCUUUUCCUCUGGGGAGAAGCAAAUUCAUGAUGUGUGUGCUGGAGAUCUGGCACUCAUGGCCAGUGCUUUCCAGUAUCUUGAACUCUUCGGGGGUCCUGUUGACCCAUUUCGUGACCUACCUCCGUGACUGCUCUUUUUCCUCUGUCUCUUAAGUGUGAUGGUUUUCCAGAGUCCAAUCCUCAGGACUUUCCCGUCCACACACAGGCCUGGUAGUCAGGUGGCUCUAAACCAUUAGGUGGGUUGUAGACCUCUCUCAAGCUGCCACCUCCUUGCUGUCGCCAGAUCGUAUUUCAGUCUGUCAGGGGUUAUCUGUAUCUGGAGGUUCCACUGUUGCUUCAGUCUCAGUUACUUAGAAUGGAACCCAGAGUCCUGCCCCUUUCCACCUACAUGCUCUUACUUGAAAGCACCUGAGACUUAUUGGGUCCCUGAUUCCUGCUUCGUCUGUAUCCGCAGAGUAGUUGCAUGUCAUUUGGCCUGUUUUCUAAAUAAUCCCACAUCAUGUCCUCCCUGCACUUACAUUGCCACUGCUCUGAUUUGGGCUUUUUUUUUUUUGGGACAAUGCCUCUGUCCCAAUUCUGAGUAACAGCUCUGGUUCUUGCCACUACCAGAGUUCUCUAGCAAAUCUGAGCAUCUGACAGGGUGAAAAAUUCUGAAUGGCUUCCUGAUGCCUGACUUUAUGGGAUCAAAUUCAAGUUGCACGCUGGCACUCAGUGCCCUUCUGGUAUCAUCUGCCAAGACCAGGGCCUGCUUCACCACAGCCACAAUAAAGUCCUUUCAAGCCCUGAUAAUGCCAUGUUUUGUCCUAACCUUUUGCUGCAGUUAAUUACUCUUCCUAUUAUCUUCCAUGAACUUAAGACUGGGCAAAAAUGUUUCCUUAUCUGUGAGCCACUCUGAACACAAACAGGUCAUGAAGAUAGUGUUGAAAACAAUAAAUGACAACCAAAAGAAAAGUGAAUAUUACCUAGUACAAAUAGUGUAAAUUGAGACAGAAAAUGUUAAAGCUAGAAAGCAAGGGCAAUAUUCUAGAAUACAAAUAGUGCUUGCCUACUACAAUAUUAAUCCCAAAUCCUUUAAAUAUACCCAUUAUAGAAGAUGCUUACCCAGCGUCAAGAGUAUAAAAGUGGGUUUGUUUGUUUUCUUGAGACAGGGCUUUGCUCUGUUGCCCAGGCUGGAGUGCAGUGGCGUGAUUGUAGCUCAAUGCAGCCUUGAAUUCCUGUGUUCAGGCGAUCCUCCGGCUUCAGCCUCUGGAGUAGCUGGGACUACAGGUGCAUGCUGCCACGCCCAGCUAAUGUUGCAGUUUUUCGUAAAGACUGGAUCUCUGUGUUACCCAGGCUGGUCUCCUGGGCUCAAGCAGUCCUCCUGCCUUGACCUCCCAAAGUGCUGGGAUUACAGGCAUGAGCCACCAUGUCCUGACCCCAGUUUGUUUUAAAGCCAAGCGAUGCACCAAGAUGUUUGUGUGCACAUCUGACAGUGGUAAUCUUUGGGUCAGGGAAUUAUAGAUAAAUUUUCUUUAAAUUUUUUCUGAGCUUUCUAAAAUCAGCUGAAAAUAAAACCUUAUUUUUUUA